AUAAUAAUUAUACAUAAAAUUACUAUAUAUAAAUUACUAUUAUUAUUACAGCUAUGAUAAGUGCUUUCUGUACAUUACCUCAGGUACCUUGAGAGGUAAUUAUUUUUUAUCCCCUUUGUGAAAUAUAGUUCAGAGAAAUUAAAAACCUUGGCCAAGGGCAUAUAACUAAUUAGUUGCAGAGAGGCUAGAAUCCAACCUCACUAGUUAUUUGCUCUCAUAUCAAGAACAAGCUCAUUAAAUAUCUCUGAAUUUCUAGUACAGUGGCUGAUCCAUAGUAAGUGUUCAGUACUAUUAGUUGACUCCGAAAGCAUCCAAUAGAUACUGUUUGUUUAUAACGUUUGUGCAAACGUAAUCAUAUGCUGUAAAAGCAGUUUGCUAAUAAAAGAAUCCUUUUCUGGACACUUUUGUAAAGCUAGAGAGAAUGCUCAACCAUUGAUUUACAUCCUCUAUGAGGAGAUAAUGAAUUGUUUUUUUUCAAAGCAGUACAUCUGCUUAUACUGCCUUGCCACCCCCUUCUAUUCUGCCUGAAUUUUUUUUUUUUUUUUUUUUUGGAACAGAAGCUCACUCUGUCACCCAGGUGGAGUGCAGUGGCAUGAUCUCGGCUCACUGCAACCUCUGCCUCCCAGGUUCAAGAGAUUCUCCUGCCUCAGCCUCCUGAGUAGCUGGGAUUACAGGUGCCUGACACUGCUCCUAGCUAAUUUUUUUAUUUUAGUAGAGACGGGGUUUCACUAUGUUGGCCAGGCUGGUUUCAAACUCCUGACCUCAGGUGAUCCGCCUGCCUCGGCUGGCCUCCCAAGGUGCUGGGAUUACAGGCGUGAGCCACCAUGCCCAGCUAUUCAGUCUCAUGCUUUUUCUGAGGACAUUUUCCUGGGCUGAUUUUGUGAGAUAUAGUAGGUUGGUGCAAAAGUGAUUGUGGUUUUUCCCAUUACUUUUAAUAGCAAAAACAGCAAUUACUUUUGCACCAACCGAAUGUGGCAGGAUGGUGAAAGGAAAGAGUACUGGCUUAGAAGUGGGAAGAUUCUAUCUACUCAUUUAACCACAAGGAGCCUUUGUUUCCUAAUAUUUAAAAUGAUGAAAUUUUAAAAAAUAGGAAGGACUUCUGGUUUCAGCUCCAACAUAUAAAAAGCUUGGAAGUCAGCACUUUUAUCUUACAACAAGAAAAAAACGGACCAAACUGAUUAUCAAUGGCUUUUCUUGGACCUGUCAGAGAAUUGAGGUCACAGGGAAAACCACCACCUCAAAAUCUAGAGAGACAGAUGAAUGCAGGAAAUCACAGCUGAGAUCUCCUUCCUGAAAGCAGAAGCGACAAUGCCAUAUCAAAUGUAGUAACUCUGAAGGAUUGCUGGAAGCAGUGCAUAGAGUAGUGUGAGAGUGAGAAACUCCUGGGAGCCACAGUCAGGGACCCCACAUUUUGUUUAGGUUUUACCUCCAGCUACCCCACCGGGGUCUGACAAUGAAAACCCAAGAAGUGCUCUCAUGCUUCCAGCAGGGGAGGGGAAAAGUGACCACUCUGAAGCAGAUCCAGAAUGUUCUCCAUAAUAAGACCUACCACAGCAAGGGAAAAGAUUGAUCAGAGCCUCAUCCAAUAUGAGGGGAGAGAAAUAACCCAACUCCAGCUCCCUCUAGCCUUCCUGUGUCACCUAAGGGGAAACAAAAUAGUUGAGAAACACUUGUAAAGGCCACCCCAGGUACACAGGCCUAAAAGAGACUUAACCAUAUGAUAACAGAAUGCUCCCACUAUCCUUACGCCCUGCCACCACAUCAACAGGUGUCCAGCGUAAUAGCCAAAAGUUAGAGCUGAAAGAGCUGCAAGGCUUAGACUCUAUAUAAGAAGGAAUGUUUAGGGAAACCCAAAGACAACAGCAGAGACAGAAACAAGGACACUAGUGGAAAUUGAAGGCUUUGACACCUACAACUACAGCAAACAUUAAACACAGCCCAACUCCUAGCCAAAUUAAUACAAAACCUCACACUAAAGGCCUGUUUAUCUCAGCUUCUAUUACUCAAUACAUCAUGUCUGCUUUUCAACCAAAUAUUACAAGUCAUGCUAGAAGGAGGAAAAAAACACAGUCUGAAGAGACAAAGAACCAGACUCAGAUAUGGGAGAGAUUUUGGAAUUAUCAGACCAGGAAUUUAAAAUAAUUAUGAUUAAAAAGUCAAACUCACAGAAGUAGAGUAGAAUGGUGGCUACCAGAGGCCAUAGAGGGGUGGGUAGAUGGGGAAAGAGGAGAUAUUGGUAAACAAGUACAAAGUUUCAGUUAGAUAUGAGGAAUAAAUUCUGGUAUUCUAUUGCACAGCAUGGUGACUGUAGUUAACAUAAACGUAUUGAAUGUCCCAAAAUAGCUAAGAGAGGAUUUUUAAAUGUUCUCACUGCAAAAAAAUGAUAAAUAUUUGAGGUGAUAGAUAUGCUAAUUAGCCUGAUUUGAUCAUUUCACAAUGUAUACAUGUACAGAAACAUCACAUUGUACUUCAUAAAUAUAUACAAUUAUUAUUUUUCAAUUAAAAAUAAAAUAAAACUUAAAAUAAUUAUGGCUAAUAUGCUUAGAUCUCUAAUGGAAAAAGUAGACAACAUCCAAGUAUAGAUGGGUAAUGUAAUCAGAGAAGUGGAAACUUACAAAGAACCUUUUAAAAUGCUAAAAAUAAAACAAAAAAAAAAUGGUACCAGAAAGGAAGAAUGUCUUGAAUGGCCUCAUCAAUAGAUUGGACAAAGCUGAGGAAGGAAUUAGUGAGCUUGAAGAUAAUGUCAGUAGAAACUUCCCAAAAUGAGAUGCAAAGAGAAAAAAAGAGUGAAAAGAAAAUAGAACAGGAUAUCUAAACUAUGGAACAUUUUCAAAAAAUAUAACAUACACAUACUGGAAUACCAAAAGGAGAAGAAAGAGAUAAUGGAACUGAAAAAAUAUUUGAAAUAAUAAUGACCAAUAAUUUUUCAAGAUUAAGGAGACACCAAACCACAAAUCCAAGAAACUCAGAGAACACCAAGUAGGGUAAAUACCAAGAAAUCUAUACCUGGGUAUGUCAAAUUCACACUACGGAAAGCCAAAGAUGAAGGAAAACCUUAAAAGCAGCCAGAGAGGGGAAAAACAAACUAUGCAAACAAGAAGAAAGUGAAGUAAAAUAUUUAAAGUAUUGAAAGAAAAAAUCCCAGCAGUCUAGGAUUCUAUAUCCAGAGAAAUUCACUUCAAAGUGAAAGAGAAAUAAAGACUUUAUCAGGCAAACAAAAAAUGAGGAAUUCAUUACCAGUAGUUCUGACCUGUAAGAAGUGUUUUUUAAAAGUUCUUCAGAAAGAAGUAAAGUGAUUUAGGCCAGAAACUCAGAUAAUCUACAUAAAGAAAGAAAGAAUGUCAGAGAAAGAAUAAAUAGAGAUAAAAUAAAACUUUUUCUUUCUUUCUUUCUUUUAUUUUUUAUUUUGAGACAGAGUCUCGCUCUGUCGCUGGAGUACAAUGGUGUGAUCUCGGCUCACUGUACCCGUCGCCUCCUGGGUUCAAGCAAUUCUCCUGCCUCAGCCUCCCGAGUAGCUGGGAUUACAGGUGCCUGCCCCAACACCCAGCUAAUUUUUGUAUUUUUAGUAGAGACGAGGUUUCACCAUGUUGGUCAGGCUGGUCUCAAACUCCUGACCUCAUGAUCCGCCCACCUCAGUCUCCCAAAGUGCUGGGAUUACUGGCAUGAGCCACCUCACCCGGCCCUAUUUCUUUUUCUUAAUUCCUCUAAUAGAUUAAUUGUUCAAAGUAAACAUAGGAACAGUGUAUUGGGUGAUUAUGUUAUAUGGAUAACUGAAAUGAAUGAUAGCAGUAUUAUAAGAAAUGGGAGGGAGGAAUUGGGAUUUCUGUUAUAAGGUACCUAUAAUACCAACAAAGCUGUAAGUGUUAUUUGAGAACGGACUUGGAUUAGUUAUGGAUGUAUUUUGCAACUCUGGAGAAACCACUAGAAAUAAUUGUAAAGGAGUAUAAUUGAUAUACUAAUAGAGGAGAGAAAAUGGAAUCUCAUAAAAUACCCAGUUAAAACCAGAGAAGGCAGAGAGAGAGGGAGAAAGAUGCAAGGAACAAGUGCAACAAAUAGAAAAUAGUUACAUACAUGGUAGAUAUUAAUCCAACUAUAUCAAUAAUCACUUCAAAUGUGAAUGGUCUAAAUAUAAAAAUUAAAAUACAAAGAUUUUCAGAGUGGAUUAAUUUACAAAAACAAGAUGCAAUUAUAUGUUGUUACAGAUAUAUCAACAGUAAAGAUUUGGAAAAAGAUAUUCCAUACUAACACUAAUCAAAAGAAAGCUGGACCAGCUAUAUUAAUUUCAGACAAAGUGGACUUCAGAACAAGGAAAAUUAUCAGGGAUAAGAAAGGGCAUUUGGCUUGGCACAGUGGCUCAUGCCUGUAAUUCCAGCACUUUGAGAGCCCAAGGUAGGAGGACUGCUUGAGCCAAGAGCUCGAGACCAGCUUGGGCAACAAAGUGACACCUUAUCUCUACCAAAAAAAAAAAAAAAUUAGCCAGAUGUAGCGGCAGGCACCUGUAGUUCCAGCUACUUGGAGGCUGAGGAGGGAGGAUCGCUUGAGCCUAGGAGUUCAAAACCAGCUUGGGUAACAUGAUGAAACCCCAUCUCUAUAAAUAAUUUAAAAAUUAGCCAGGCAUAGUGGCAUGCUCCUGUAGUCCCAGCUACUCCAGAGGCUGAGAUGGGAAAAUGGCUUGAGCCCAGGAGGUCAAUGCUGCAAUGAGCCAUGAUCUCUCCACUGCACUCCAGCCUGGGCAGCGGAGUGAGACUCUGCCUCAAAAAAAGAAAGAAAGAAAGGGCAUUACAUAAUGAUAAAGGGGUCAGUUAUUCAAGAAGAAAUUCUUAAUAUGUAUGCAUCUAACAAAAGAGCAUCAAAAUAUGUGAGACAAAAACUGAUAGAACUGCAAAGAGAAAUCAACAAAUUGACCAUUAUAGUUAAAGAUUUUAAUACAUCUUUUAGUAGUUGAUGGAUCAAGCAGGCAUAAAAUUAGUAAGGACAUAAUUGACUGAACAGUUCCAUUCAUCAGCUUGCUCUAAAUGAUAUUUAUAGAAUACUUCAUCCAACAACAACAGAGUAUAUAUUCUUCUUGACAUCACAUGGAACAUUCACCAAAAUACACCACAUUCUGAGCCAUAAAACACUCCAAAAUAAAUUUAAAAGAAUAGAAAUUAUACAAUCUAUGCUCUCAAACCACAAUGAAUUAAACUAGAAAUUAAUAACAGAAAGCAUGGAAAAUUCCAAAAUAUUUUCAGAUUAAAUAACAUAAUACUAAAUAACACAUGGGUCAAAGAAGAAACUCCAGAGAAAUUUUAAAAUAAUUUAAAUGAAAAUGAAAAUGCAACUUAUCAAAAUUUCUGGGAUGCAGCAAAAGCAGUGCUUAGAGGAAAAUUUAUACCAUUGAAUGCAUAUAUUAGAAAAGAAGAAAAGUCUAAAAUCAAUAAUCUAAAAAUCCACCUGAGGAAACUAGAAAAGGAAGAGUAAUUUAUGCCUACAACAAACAGAAAAUAAAUAAUAUAAAUUUUGGCAAAAAUUGAUGAAAUUAAAAAUAGGAAAUCAGUAGAGGAAACACAAUGAAACCAAAAGCUGGUUCUUUGAAAAGAUCAAUAAAUCUGAUAAACCUCUAGCCAGACUAACCAAGAAAAAAAAAAGAGAAAACACAAAUUACUAAUAUUAUAAAAGAAAAUUGGGCUAGGCUUAGUGACUCACACCUGUCAUCCCAGCACUUGGGAGGCUGAGGUGGGAGGAUCACUUGAGGCCAAGUGUUCAAGACCAGCCUGGGCAACAUAAUGAGACCCCAUCUCUACAAAAAAUUUGAAAAUUAGCCAGGCAUCAUGGCACGUGCCUGUAGUCCUAGCUACUCAGGAGGCUGAGGCAGGAGGAUUGCUUAAGCCCAGGAGUUGGAGGUACAGUGAGCUAUGGUUGUGCCACUGCAUUCCAGCCUGGGUCACAGAGAGAGGCCCUGUCUCCCUGAAAAAAGAGAAAAGAAAAUGAGAUCAUCAUUACUAAUCCCAUGGACAUAAAAAGAAAAGGCUACAAACAAUUCUGUGCACACAAAUUUGGAUAAAUUAGAUGAGGUGGGCUAAUUCUUUGAAAGACACAAACUAUACCAAAACUCGCACAAGGAGAAAUAGAUGAACUGAAUAGGCCUAUAUCAAUUUAAAAUUUCAAUCAAUAAUUAAUAACCUUCCAAAAAAGAAAGCACCAAGCCCAGGUUGUUUCACUGGUAAAUUCUACCAAACAUUUAAAGAAGAAAUGAUACCAGUUCUCUACAAUCUCUCCCAGAAAAUAGAAACAGAGGGAGUACUUGCAAAUUCAUUCAUUGAGGCCAGCAUUACCCUCAUAAAAAAACCAGAAAGACAAAGUUGGAGGACUGACACUGCCCAAUUUCAAGACUUACCAUAUGAAGACAUUACAAGGAAAGGAAACUGUAGACCAAAAUCUCUCAAAAACAUAAAUCCAAAAAUCUUCAUCAAAAUAUUAGCAGAGCAAAUCCAACAAUGUAUAAAAUGAAUUAUACACCACAAUCAAGUGAGAUUUAUUCCAGAUAUGAAAGGCUGACUCAACAAUUAAAAAUCAAUUUAUGUAAAUAAUCACAUCAAGAGGCUAAAGAAGAAAGUCCUGUGAUCAUAUCAAUAGAUGUAGCAGAAGCAUUUGGCAAGGUCUAGCAUGCAUUCAUGUAAAACUCUCAGCAAACUAGGAAUAAAAGGGAAUUUCCCAACUUGAUAAAGAGUGCCUACAGAAAGCCUACAACUGACAUACUUAAUGGUGAGAAACUGGAUGAUUUCCCUCUAAGAUAAGGAAGAAGGAAAGAAUGUCCUGUCUCACCACUCCUAUUCAACAUUGUGCAGGAAGUCCUUGCUAGUGCAGCAAGAUAGGAAAUAAAAGGUAUGCAGAUUAGAAAGAAAAAUUAAAACCAUCUUACAUGAUUGUCUAUAUGGAAAAUCUCAAAGAAUCAACAUAAACUCAUGGAAAUAAUAAGUGAUUAUAGCAAGGUUGGAAGAUACAAAGUAAAUAUACAAAAGUCAAUUGUUACCAGUAAUGAACCAUUAGAAUUUGAAAUUAAAACACAAUACCAUUUACAGUUGCACCAAAAAAAAUAAAUACUUAGUCAUAAAUCUAUCAAAAUAUGUACAGGAUCUAUACAGAGAAAGGAGAUAUAAAUUAAUGGAAAGAUUAUUCCAUAUUCAUAGAUUGGAAGAUUCAGUAUCAAUAUGUCCAGUCUUCCUGACUUGAUCUAUAGAUCUAUAGAUUAAACACAAUCUCAACUAAAAUCUCAGCAAGGUACUUUGUGUAUGUCAACAAACUGAUUCUACAGUUCAUGUGGAAAAGCAAAGGACCCACAAUAGACAACACAACACUGAAAGACAAAGUUGGAGGACUGACACUGCCCAAUUUCAAGACUUACUGUAAAGCUACAGUAAUAAAUAUAGCAUGGUACUGGUGAAAGAAUAGACACAUAAGUCAAUGGAACAGAAUAGAGAGCCCACAAAUAGACCCCCAAACAAAUACAGUCACUGAUCCAUGACAAAGGACAAAGGCAAUUCAAUAGAGAAAGAUAGUCUUUCCAACAAAUGGUUGUGGAACAACUGGAUUUUCACAUGCCAAAAAAAAAAAAAUAGACACAGACACAGAACAUACAAUACACCUUUUAGAAAAAUUAAUUCGAAAUGAAUCUUGGGCCUAAAUGAAAAAUGCAAAACUGUAAGACUUUGAGAAGAUAACAUAGGAAAAAAAUAUAGGUUUACUUGUAUUUGAUGAUGGGUUUUUAGAUAUGGUACCAAAAGCAUGAUCCAUGAGAGAAAAUAUAAAUAAGAUAGAUUUUAUUGAAAUUAAAAACUGCUAUGGAAAAGAUACUGUUAAGAGAAUGAGGCCAGGCAUGGUGGCUCAAGCCUGUAAUCCCUGCACUUUGGGAGGCCGAGGUGGGCAGAUCACUAGGUCAGGAGAUCGAGACCAUCCUGGCUAACACGAUGAAACCCCGUCUCUACUAAAAAAUACAAAAAAUUAGCUGGGUGUGGUGGCGGGUGCCUGUAGUCCCAGGUACUCGGGAGGCUGAGGCAGGAGAAUGGCGUGAACCCAGGAGGAGGAGCUUGCAGUGAGCCGAGAUCACGCCACUGCGCUCCAGCCUGGGCGACAGAGCGGGACAACAUCUCAAAAAAAAAAAAAAAAAAAAAAAAAAAAGAAUAAAAAAACAAGCCAGACUUGGAGAAAAUAUUUGCAAACACAUAUAUCUGAUAAAGGACUUGUAUCCAAAAUAUACUUAAAACUCAACCACGAGAAAACAACUCAUUAAAAAUGGCAAAAGAUCUGGAUUAACUUAUGUAAUUAAUUACACAUGUAAUUAAUUAAUUCCUACUAAGGAAAACUUACAGAUGGCAAAUAUGCAUAUGAAAAGGAGCUCAUCAUCUCAUCGUGUCAUUAGAGAAUUAAGGCAAUAAUAAGAUAACACUACACACCUAUUAGAAUAGCUAAAAUUCAAAAAACUGACAAUACCAAAUACUGAUGACAAUGUGGAGUAGCAGGAACUCUCGUUGUUGGGAAUGCAAAUAAUGGUAAAGCUAUUUUUGAAGGCUGUUUGGCAGUCUCCCACAAAGCUAAACAUAGGCUUACUAUAUAAUCACUCUACCGGGUAUUUACCCAGUUAAAUUGAAAACCUACAUUCACACAAAAACCUGCAUGCAAAUAUUUACAGCACCUUUAUUCAUAAUUGCCCAAAACUGGUAGCAACCAAGAUAUCCUUUAAAAGCUGGAUAAAUAAACUGUGGUACAUUCAUGCAAUGGAAUACUAUUCAAUAAUAAAAAGAAAUAAGCUAUUGUGUCAUGAAAAAACAUGGAUGAACUUUGGUGAAACAAGUCAUAGUGAAACAAACCAAUGUGAAAAAGCUACAUACUGUAUGGUUUCAAUUAUAUGACAUUCUGAAAACCACAAAACUAUAGAGACAGCAAAACAAUCAGUGGUUUGAGGGGAAGAGAGGAAAAUAAAUAGGUCAGGAAUUCUGGAGUAGUAAAAUUAAUUUGUGUAAUAUUGUAUUUGUGGGUACAAUAUAUUAUGCAUUUGUCAAAUGUCAUAGAGCUGUACAGCACAAAAACCGGACUUCAAAAUAGGAACAUUUUUAAGAAUCAUUUAGGAGGUUGGGGGAUUCCAGGGAGAAAUGCAGACUGUGCAAGGGGAUCUAACUGCAUUAAAAAUAUGGAAAACAACCUCACUGAAGGGUAGAGAGGGGAAAAGUAUCGCCCCCUCUUUAAGUAACUUUGGAAAUGAGCAGAGUCUGUAAGAUGAAGGCAAUAGGAACUGCAAAAAAGUACUGUAUUCCACUUGAUAAAAUUGUUCCCCGUGGGGAUACAAAUUAACAAUUAUCAUACUGCUGUGUAUGUACACAGGAAUUGAACAAUUAAGUAAAUAGCAGCUAGUGGGAGCCAGGUUACUUACUGUUGGAAUGCGAGUUUACAGAAAAGCAAGGGAUGGAAGUUAGAAAAAAAGUAGGAAGUGCACUUAUAGUAAUAUGUGUAAAAGCUUUGUAUACUGCAUGUAUUAUUAUUUAUGCAUAUUAUUUUUACCCUGAAGGUAUUAUUCAUUAUAAAGGAUUAUUAUUUUCACAUUCUUUUAUGCAUAAUUCAGAUCAUGUACUUAAAGAGGACACAGACUAAUUCAAAAAGCUCAGAAUAUUUUCAGAUACAACUUUUUAACAAGUAUGCCCGUCUUCUGAGGUGGUCUUUUAAAUUUGUCUAGAUAGAUUAUGUUCUGCGGUCUGUAGGAGCUGUGUACAUCAGAGCAGCUUAUUAUAAAUACCUAAAGCAAAAGAAAUGGUUUAUUUAGAAAAUAAAGUAUAGAAAUAUAAUGUUAACUGCUCCUGUGUGAUGUCAAAAGUGGAAAGAAGGUGGGAAAUUCUUAUUUCAUGUGGGAUACUACUAAAUACCUGGAUGUUUUCAAGUAGUCGCAUUUUUAGCACAGCAUAGUCCAAGCAUCCGGGUAUUUGAAUUUUUCCCUUUCCAGCUGGUAAUCUUGAUAUGUUAUAGAUGUAGGCAAAGCCUCAAAGUUAAAUCAUUUCCAAAUGCUUUGAACAGCAUUUAACUAGAAAUAAAAUUUCAUUCAACAUCACCCUCUCCACCUUCUUUUAUGUGCAGUUACUUUCCGUAUCUGCAGCAAGUAGACAGAAGAGUGCCAAAAAAGAAUCCUUCUCUGACUUCACAAAUCAGUAGAAGGCCUGAUGACUACAUGCCCAGAACUUGGGUUUCAGACACACUAUUAACUUGCCUCAAUACAGUGCAAAUAAUUUUCCAGAUUGAAGCAUUGCUCUAUUUAAAUCAACCUUCCUGCCUAUUAAUAGCUGUGAAAUACUAGAAAAUAUUACUGGGCCAAUAAAGCAUUGUGUCUGCUCAAAUCUUUUUAAAAUGAGGCAAGACACAAAUACAUACAUACUUAAAUACAUAUGUAUAUAACAUUGCAGAACCUCCUUUAAAAGUUUAAAUAACAAAAUCAGCCAUCUAGAUUGAUGUGGAGAUUAAAAAAAGUGAACCAACUGAAUUUCUAAGGAACCUUUGUAUGCCAAUAUUCCAUUUCCAUAUUUUCUUCUUCUUCUUUGUUUUUUGUUUUUUGUUUUUGUUUUUUUUUUUUGAGACAGAGUCUUGCUCUGUUACCCAGGCUGUAGUACAGUGGCAGGAUGUCGGCUCACUGCAACCUCCGCUUCCCAGGUUCAAACAACUCUCACGCUUCAGCCACCCAAGUAGCUGGGAUUCCAGGCGUGUGCCACCUCGCCCAGCUAAUUUUUGUAUUUUUAGUAGAGAUGGGGUUUCACCAUGUUGCCCAGGCUGGUCUCAAACUUCUGGCCUCAAGGGAUCCACCCAUCUCGGCCUCCCAAAGUCCUCAGAUUACAGGCAUGAGUCACCACGUGCCAACCCAUACUUUCUUCCUACUUGCUUUAUAUUCACACUCUCCUUCAUUGUCUUUUACUAAUAGCAGCAUUGUUUCCUGGGUAUUUUUUUAUGAUAAUUUUCUGCUUACCUCUGAGCACACCACUGCCCUCCCUCCACCAUCCCACCACCCUCCACACACAAAUGAUUGCAGAUAGUUUGGGAUUUGCAGUGCAGAGGAAAUGAACACACAUAAUUUAUUUAUUUUUUUCUUUUUUUCCUUGUUUCCUUCCUUCCUUCCUUCCUUCCUCCCUCCCUCCCUCUCUCUCUUUCUUUCUCUUUCCUUCUUUCUUUUAAUAUUGCAUGGCCCAUUCAUCAUUCUGUACAAUUAGCCAAAUGAAAGGUAUCUUUGUUUUAGCUUGAUCUGUAAUUCUUUUCAGAUUCAUUAUGUGCAUGGCAACACAAAGAAACCAUGGUACUUUUGGGCAGCAUCUGAUUCAUCAGGAAAUUCCUCCUGCUAUGAUAUGUGGUUGGGGAGAACGUGAGUGAUGUGAUCCAGAUGCAUGAGCCACCCGUUGCCAGUAGUGCAGAUGUGUUUUAUACACACAUGCCCAGAUGGUGACCCCUGUGGCAUUAUUAAUGAGUUCCAGAUGCCAGGCUUCCUUCUUUGCAUGUAUGUGCCUCGAUUUCAUAUAUUUCAUGUGUUUAUUUAUGAGGGACAGCAUUCCUACAUUUCAUAUAUGGCAGUUACUAUUUAAAAUGAGAAAUUUUAACUGCUCUGGAAAUUGAUAAAGAAUCUUUUAAAUUGAUAUGAAAUGUGUCUCUCAUUUCAAAAUGACUAGCCAUGCAAUCACUGAAUUCACAGAGCAAAUUACUGAACUUUCCCUUCAUAUAUUGAGAAAAUAUGGUGCUGAGUUACAUUUUAAAGAUAGUUAAGAAAUAAAAUAUUUGCACACAUAAUACAUUCUAAUGAUUUUUUGCUUUCUUUUCCUUUUUGAUCUCCAAAGCCUAUUUUUAAAAGUACAAUGUCUGUACAUUGAACAUUGUUACUCACUAUUAAUUAAAUCUAGGCAUCAAGAGAAAUUUGACAUCUUCUAGAAAUUGUUCAUACUUAUGGAUUUACAGGAAGAGAACUGGUUUUAUUAAAAUAUAGUCCAGCUGUGGCUCCAAACUAUCAUGGAUUGUAACUCCAUGGAUUAGAAGAAAUUGAUUAGUCUUAUAUUUUGGCUUAGAUCUAAAGUAUAAAAUAUAAGAGCAUAGUAGUUCCACUGAAUUAAAAUGAACCAACUCAAGUUUUUAUUUUAAAAAACUCCAGUAUUUUAUGGGGAAAUAAAAAAAUGAAACAAAUUCUUAAAAUAGAAAGAGGAAAAAUGCAAACGACAGAUGAUCAGACUUUGAAAGAUGAAGUUCAUGUCCAUUUCCUUCUUUACUACCAGAAGUAAUGAUCUUUUAAGUCAGCAAAUGUAUAAUUUAUGAUAAAGAACUAUCUCCAAAAUCAGCUACAGAAAAUAAAUGACCAAUAUGCUGAUAAGAUUUUUGUUAAGGUGCUACCCACUUUUUUUUUUUUAAGACAGGGUCUAACUCUGUCACCCGGUGCAGUGUCAUGAUCUCAACUCACUGCAGCCUUGACCUCAAGGGCUCAGGUGGUCCUCCCACCUCAGCCUUCUGAGUAGCUGGGACUACAGGCACAUACCACCACGUCUGGCUAAUUUUUGUAGAGACAGGGUUUGGCCAUGUUGCCCAGGCUGGUCUCAAGCUCCUGAGCUCAAGAAAUUCAUCCACCCCCGCCUCCCAAACUGCUGGGAUUACAGGCAUGAGCCACCACACCAGGCCAUGGUGCUGCAUACUUUUACUGUCAAUAGCAGAGGGUCAAAGUUGCUGAAUGCUUAAGUAAGCACAUCUUGAGUCUUGGUUACUUAGCAUAUGGUUUCGGGUCCUCUUGAAAACUAUUCUACUUCCUUAAGUAAAGCUUGUUUUUCCUAUUUGUGUAUGUGUAUUUAUCUCAAUUACAUAAAGGUGCUAACUCAUUCAUUUUCCACACCCACAAAGUAGGAUGGAAAUUUAAAGCAGUUAUCUGAUAAAUGGAGGCAAGAUUAGUGGAUUUUUUUCCCUGAAAGUAUUCCUUGAAGUUAAAAAACAAAAAUUGAAGUUAUAGGAUUUGUUCCCGAACUCCUCAGAUACUCACCUCAGACUUGCUCCGUGUGUGUUUUUGUUUAAGUGCAUAUCUAUGAUAACAACUCUAGGGUUCUCUGAAAGAAGAUUCAGAGCAAUUCUAAGAAGACUUCAGAUCAUUUAUGAGGAUGGAGCAAUCAAAGGAGAAUGCUGGUGACCUUGUUGCAGAUGUGGGUUGUCCCCUUAUAUUUCACGAUAAAAUUAUACUGGUGGCGGUUUCUGUCUAUGUGGGGGAUGUUCUCCGUUAUUACCAGUUACAUCCUCUUCAGAGCUACCCGAAAACCCCUCUCAGGAAGGACACCACGAUUGGUCUACAAAUGGUUUCUUUUGAUCUACAAACUCAGCUAUGCAUUUGGUGUUGUGGGUUACUUGGCGAUCAUGUUUACAAUGUGUGGAUUCAAUCUGUUUUUCAAAAUCAAAGCUAGAGAUUCCAUGGAUUUUGGCAUUGUGUCUUUGUUCUACGGCCUCUACUAUGGAGUAAUGGGGAGAGACUUUGCCGAGAUCUGCUCAGACUACAUGGCUUCCACUAUAGGGUUCUACAGUGUCAGCCGGUUGCCUACAAGGAGCUUAUCGGACAAUAUCUGUGCAGUCUGUGGGCAGAAGAUCAUUGUGGAGCUUGAUGAAGAAGGGCUCAUUGAAAACACCUACCAGCUUUCCUGUAAUCAUGUCUUUCAUGAAUUCUGCAUCCGAGGUUGGUGUAUCGUUGGGAAAAAGCAGACUUGCCCUUACUGCAAAGAGAAAGUUGAUUUGAAGAGGAUGAUCAGUAAUCCCUGGGAGCGCACACAUUUUCUGUAUGGACAAAUCCUGGAUUGGCUUCGUUAUUUGGUGGCCUGGCAACCUGUGGUGAUAGGAAUAGUUCAAGGCAUUAUCUAUUCACUAGGGCUGGAAUAGGACAGCAGACCCCAGAAGCAACAUACUGCAUGGUUGAAAUCCUUGGUCCAACAUUUAAUAUUAAUUUUUUUAAUUUUAGAGAUGAUCCCAAGUGUUUAGAAAACUAAGUAAACUUUGUUGUCAAGCAAUUUGUCCAUGUGGAAAGAAUUUAAAGAGAAGCUGAACAAUGGAAUAAACAAAUAAAGCAUGUUUUUUCAUCUUUCCCAUUA